GUAUCCUUAGCUCGGCUCCUCGCUUCCCCAGCGGCUCGCCCCAGACAUUGCACCGCGGAGGGGAGGCCGGUCGACCUCUCCGGCGAUGCCCGGCUUCUGCCUGCUGUGGGAGGGCAGCGGCGGGCACCGUGAUCUCCGCACCGAGAAGAGCUCCCCUUGCCCUCUAGUCGAAGCUCCCGAGUGCUCGGAGCACGCUCACCCCUCGCGAACACACCCCUGCAGCCGAAGCAGCCCCUGAAGCCCGCAGCGCCUGCAACAGGUCCGGGGCAGUGGGGGAAACUUACAGCAGUGGCGACUGGCCGCAACGCACAACUGAGUUCUAGCGACGGUCACGGGCAAGGAGGCGACGAACCGGUCGUCUCAGCCCAGGGAAGCGGUGGCGAAUGCCCCGGAGAAAGGAGGGCCAGCCGGGGAGAGGACUGCGCCCCGAACGAUGGCUCGCGGACCGGCUACCGAUGGCGUUCGCCUCCGUCUGUCGUCCCCACGCCGCGGACCCGGUGUCCAGGACCCGCAGAGCGUCUCCGGAGCGCGUCACGAUAUCAUGGCUAUAUUUUUGGUUUCUACAAGUGGCAUCAUGAACCUGCUGAAUUCCAGGCUAAAACCCAGGUUCAGCAACUUCUUGUCUCAAUCACCCUUCAGUCAGAGUGUGAUGCUUUCCCCAACAUAUCUUCAGAUGAGUCUUAUACUUUACUUGUGAAAGAACCAGUGGCUGUCCUUAAGGCCAACAGAGUUUGGGGAGCAUUACGAGGUUUAGAGACCUUUAGCCAGUUAGUUUAUCAAGAUUCUUAUGGAACUUUCACCAUCAAUGAAUCCACCAUUAUUGAUUCUCCAAGGUUUUCUCACAGAGGAAUUUUGAUUGAUACAUCCAGACAUUAUCUGCCAGUUAAGAUUAUUCUUAAAACUCUGGAUGCCAUGGCUUUUAAUAAGUUUAAUGUUCUUCACUGGCACAUAGUUGAUGACCAGUCUUUCCCAUAUCAGAGCAUCACUUUUCCUGAGUUAAGCAAUAAAGGAAGCUAUUCUUUGUCUCAUGUUUAUACACCAAAUGAUGUCCGUAUGGUGAUUGAAUAUGCCAGAUUACGAGGAAUUCGAGUCCUGCCAGAAUUUGAUACCCCUGGGCAUACACUAUCUUGGGGAAAAGGUCAGAAAGACCUCCUGACUCCAUGUUACAGUAGACAAAACAAGUUGGACUCUUUUGGACCUAUAAACCCUACUCUGAAUACAACAUACAGCUUCCUUACUACAUUUUUCAAAGAAAUUAGUGAGGUGUUUCCAGAUCAAUUCAUUCAUUUGGGAGGAGAUGAAGUGGAAUUUAAAUGUUGGGAAUCAAAUCCAAAAAUUCAAGAUUUCAUGAGGCAAAAAGGCUUUGGCACAGAUUUUAAGAAACUAGAAUCUUUCUACAUUCAAAAGGUUUUGGAUAUUAUUGCAACCAUAAACAAGGGAUCCAUUGUCUGGCAGGAGGUUUUUGAUGAUAAAGCAAAGCUUGCGCCGGGCACAAUAGUUGAAGUAUGGAAAGACAGCGCAUAUCCUGAGGAACUCAGUAGAGUCACAGCAUCUGGCUUCCCUGUAAUCCUUUCUGCUCCUUGGUACUUAGAUUUGAUUAGCUAUGGACAAGAUUGGAGGAAAUACUAUAAAGUGGAACCUCUUGAUUUUGGCGGUACUCAGAAACAGAAACAACUUUUCAUUGGUGGAGAAGCUUGUCUAUGGGGAGAAUAUGUGGAUGCAACUAACCUCACUCCAAGAUUAUGGCCUCGGGCAAGUGCUGUUGGUGAGAGACUCUGGAGUUCCAAAGAUGUCAGAGAUAUGGAUGACGCCUAUGACAGACUGACAAGGCACCGCUGCAGGAUGGUCGAACGUGGAAUAGCUGCACAACCUCUUUAUGCUGGAUAUUGUAACCAUGAGAACAUGUAAAAAAUGGAGGGGAAAAAGGCCACAGCAAUCUGUACUACAAUCAACUUUAUUUUGAAAUCAUGUAAAAUAAGAUAUUAGACUGUUUUUUGAAUAAAAUAUUUUUAUUGAUUGAA